AGUUGCUUUGAGGCAGUACCGGAGGAGAAAGAUGGCGGCUACCUUACUAGCUGCUCGGGGAGCCGGGCCAGCACCGGCUUGGGGGCCGGAGGCGUUCACUCCAGACUGGGAAAGCCGAGAAGUUUCCACUGGGACCACUAUCAUGGCCGUGCAGUUUGACGGGGGCGUGGUUCUGGGGGCGGACUCCAGAACAACCACUGGGUCCUACAUCGCCAAUCGAGUGACUGACAAGCUGACACCUAUUCACGACCGCAUUUUCUGCUGUCGCUCAGGCUCAGCUGCUGAUACCCAGGCAGUAGCUGAUGCUGUCACCUACCAGCUCGGUUUCCACAGCAUUGAACUGAAUGAGCCUCCACUGGUCCACACAGCAGCCAGCCUCUUUAAGGAGAUGUGUUACCGAUACCGGGAAGACCUGAUGGCGGGAAUCAUCAUCGCAGGCUGGGACCCUCAAGAAGGAGGGCAGGUGUACUCAGUGCCUAUGGGGGGUAUGAUGGUAAGGCAGUCCUUUGCCAUUGGAGGCUCCGGGAGCUCCUACAUCUAUGGCUAUGUUGAUGCUACCUACCGGGAAGGCAUGACCAAGGAAGAGUGUCUGCAAUUCACUGCCAAUGCUUUCUUCUUUUAUCCACAGCUCUCGCUUUGGCCAUGGAGCGGGAUGGCUCCAGUGGAGGAGUGAUCCGCCUGGCAGCCAUUGCAGAGUCAGGGGUAGAGCGGCAAGUACUUUUGGGAGACCAGAUACCCAAAUUCGCCGUUGCCACUUUACCACCCGCCUGAAUCCUGGGAUUCUAGUAUGCAAUAAGAGAUGCCCUGUACUGAUGCAAAAUUUAAUAAAGUUUGUCACAGAGAA